GCAGGUUCCGGGCUGCUUAGGUUGGCACCGGUCCGUGGUCCCCGGGGGCGCAGUCGCAGCGCUCCCGCCCUCCAGGCGUCAGCGAGUGCGCGGUCCAGUGCGGCCGGAACCUGGCGCAACUCCUAGAGCGGUCCUUGGGGAGACGCGGGUCCCAGUCCUGCGGCUCCUACUGGGGAGUGCGCUGGUCGGAAGGGGGAUGGAGACAGAAGUCACAAACUCACAUGCCACCAGCCAUAUGAUGUAAACAUGUAAACUGGGCCAAGGAAUACAAAAGGGAGUGGUGAGCUGGGGACACUGAAGAAUGGAUGCCCUGUCUAGAGGAGUGAAAAUGAAGCAUUUCAUACAAACAACAUGAUUUCGGGCAAUCACUUUGGGAAUCAGGAUAAGGUGUUCCCCCAGUCUGCAGAAACACUGGCAACAUUUACAAAGCUUUAGGUUCAUUCUUGUAAGUGUUGCUGGUGUCAGAAUAGGAACCUCCCUGCGCUUUGAAGGGAUGAAUGUGACCUCUCCCACAUUCUCCGGUGCUGUGAUGUACCUUAAACACAGCAAGGGCACCUGGCCUGGGUGGAGCCCACUCCUCAGCACCCACCUCACUUCUUGCAGUAUUCUGCAGACCCCAGCCCUGUGCCUGUGCUCCUGGACAGCUGGAGAUAAGGAGUGGGCCCUGGAAGAUGCUCAUUCAGGCCCUGCUCAAGAUUCCAGUCCUGAUUGCUGGACUCGCUGAAGAGAGACUACGCAGGAAAGCCCCAGCCACCCAUCAAAUCAGAGAGAAGGAAUCCACCUUCUUACGCUAUGGCAGGUAAGAAAGUACUCAUUGUCUAUGCACACCAGGAACCCAAGUCUUUCAACGGAUCCUUGAAGAAUGUGGCUGUAGAUGAACUGAGCAGGCAGGGCUGCACCGUCACAGUGUCUGAUUUGUAUGCCAUGAACCUUGAGCCGAGGGCCACAGACAAAGAUAUCACUGGUACUCUUUCUAAUCCUGAGGUUUUCAAUUAUGGAGUGGAAACCCACGAAGCCUACAAGCAAAGGUCUCUGGCUAGCGACAUCACUGAUGAGCAGAAAAAGGUUCGGGAGGCUGACCUAGUGAUAUUUCAGUUCCCGCUGUACUGGUUCAGCGUGCCAGCCAUCCUGAAGGGCUGGAUGGAUAGGGUGCUGUGCCAGGGCUUUGCCUUUGACAUCCCAGGAUUCUACGAUUCCGGUUUGCUCCAGGGUAAACUAGCGCUCCUUUCCGUAACCACGGGAGGCACGGCCGAGAUGUACACGAAGACAGGAGUCAAUGGAGAUUCUCGAUACUUCCUGUGGCCACUCCAGCAUGGCACAUUACACUUCUGUGGAUUUAAAGUCCUUGCCCCUCAGAUCAGCUUUGCUCCUGAAAUUGCAUCCGAAGAAGAAAGAAAGGGGAUGGUGGCUGCGUGGUCCCAGAGGCUGCAGACCAUCUGGAAGGAAGAGCCCAUCCCCUGCACAGCCCACUGGCACUUCGGGCAAUAACUCUGUGGCACGUGGGCAUCACGUAAGCAGCACACUAGGAGGCCCAGGCGCAGGCAAAGAGAAGAUGGUGCUGUCAUGAAAUAAAAUUACAACAUAGCUA